AGCCCGCACCUACCGGCCAGGCCGGUCAGCUCGGUCCACAGCUCUGGCGCGGGCAGGUCUGGGCGCCGGCGACCCCGGGGCUUGCGGGCUCUCUAGGGAGGGGGCAGGGGCGCCCCUGAGGAGGGGGGCAGGCAGCCUGCUGGCCCCUUCCCUCCGCGAACCGGGCCGGAGGAUUGGGGCCGAAGUCUACGCUUCCAGCAUCGGGGCCGAGCCGAGGGUCCUCGGCACGGCCCCGUCGCCCCGCGCCCCGUGCCCGCCCCCGCCCCGGGAACCUCGGCGUGGGGGUGGGGCAGGCGGCGGGAGACGACGGGCUGCACGGCCAGCCCCGCUCACCUGGGCGGGGUCCCCGGGCUCCGCGGCCGCCGCGGCGCCACCAUCCCUGCGGAAGAGGCUGUAGAAGAUGUAGAUGAGCAACGAGUAAAAGGCGUACAUGGGAGCGCGGGGCGGCAGAGGGCCCCGCUUCGCGCCGCCCCGCGUCCCCGCGCCCAGACUCGGCGCCCGCCCGCCGCAGUGCCGGUGCGCAUGCUCGCGACGGCCGCCCCCACGGCCCGGCUCCCACGGCUGGAAGGUGUGUGCAGUGGCCUCAGGGAUCCGGAAAGUCUAGGACUGAACUUCUCCUAACAUCCAGUAAUGGGGACCUGGAACCUGGGCUUACUAGAGUGCCGCGCGUAGGGCUCCAGGUCGCUGGCUUCUGCGCUUCCUUCCUCUCCAAAGUUGAGUAUCUCCUAUCUGUGUCCUCGUACAUACUGCCGCCUGAGGUGCCAUGGCCCCCAAGCCGGGGGCCGAGUGGAGCACAGCCCUGUCCCAUCUGGUGCUGGGAGUGGUGUCUCUGCACGCAGCCGUGAGCACAGCCGAGGCAAGUCGAGGGGCUGCUGCUGGCUUCCUGCUCCAGGUCUUGGCUGCCACCACCACGCUGGCCCCAGGGCUGAGCACACACGAAGACUGCCUUGCUGGAGCCUGGGUGGCCACCGUCAUCGGCCUUCCCCUUCUGGCCUUCGAUUUCCACUGGGUGAAUGGGGACCGCUCCUCUGCCAACCUGCUCCUGGGAGGAGGCAUGGUGCUGGCAGUGGCUGGCGGCCACCUCGGCCCUGAGGGCCGCUCUGUGGCUGGUCAGGCAAUGCUGUUGGUGGUCGCAGUGACCAUCCUCAUUGUAGCUGUCUUCACGGCCAACACUUAUGGGAUGUGGGGGGGGGCGAUGCUGGGUGUGGCAGGCCUCCUGAGCCGGCUGGAGGAGGACAGGCUGCUGCUGCUACCGAAGGAGGAUGUCUGUCGCUGGGCCUUGGCUGUAGGCAGCUGGGCUUACUGCCGGGCCCUGCAUACACAGCGCCUCCAGUGGGAGUGACAGUUGGAUACAGCCAGGCAGGGUUUCUGCCCUGCCGAACACUUUCCCUCCCACCUGCCUGCUCCUGGCGCCUUCUCCCUAGGGGUAGACUCUUCUGCCUACUGAAGUGGGUUUGCUGCACAUUGACUGGUCAGGGGCAGAGUCUGGGUGCUGUCCUUUGGCCACGUGUGGGGACUUGUCUAGACCAGAAUGAAAGGGACAGGGUCCCAGACACGUUUGGGGGUCCUGAUUCUGGGCUGGACACGGUUGUGGAUCCAGAGAAGAGGCCUAGUCUCCAAUAAAUCUUAGGAAUUUUGCAGGAA